CAGUUAGAUUUGGAGGUUCAACUUCAACAUGGCCGAAGCAAGUAGCGCCAAUCUAGGCAGCGGCUGUGAGGAAAAAAGGCAUGAGGGGUCGUCUUCGGAAUCUGUGCCACCCGGCACUACCAUUUCGAGGGUGAAGCUCCUCGACACCAUGGUGGACACUUUUCUUCAGAAGCUGGUCGCCGCCGGCAGCUACCAGAGAUUCACUGACUGCUAUAAGUGCUUCUACCAGUUGCAGCCUGCGAUGACACAGCAAAUCUAUGACAAGUUUAUAGCUCAGUUGCAGACAUCUAUCCGGGAGGAAAUCUCUGACAUCAAAGAGGAGGGGAACCUAGAAGCUGUCUUGAAUGCCUUGGAUAAAAUUGUGGAAGAAGGCAAAGUCCGCAAAGAGCCAGCCUGGCGCCCCAGCGGGAUCCCAGAGAAGGAUCUGCACAGUGUUAUGGCACCCUACUUCCUGCAGCAACGGGACACCCUGCGGCGCCAUGUGCAGAAACAGGAGGCCGAGAACCAGCAGCUGGCAGAUGCCGUCCUGGCAGGGCGGAGGCAGGUGGAGGAGCUGCAGCUACAGGUCCAGGCCCAGCAGCAGGCCUGGCAGGUGCGAAGCCCAGCGGUGCAGAGUCCAGCAAAGGUGCAGCCUUUGUGUCCAAGCAGGAGGGCAGCGAGGUAGUGAAGAGACCCAGGCGCUACCUGUAUCAAUGGCUGGGAGCCCCAGUCCCCUACCCGGAUCCCCUGGAGCCCAGGAGGGAGGUGUGUGAGCUCAAUCCGGACUGUGACGAGUUGGCUGACCACAUCGGCUUUCAGGAGGCCUAUCGGCGCUUCUACGGCCCGGUCUAGGGUGUCGCUCUGCUGGCCUGGCCGGCAACCCCAGUUCUGCUCCUCUCCAGGCACCCUUCUUUCCUCUUCCCCUUGCCCUUGCCCUGACCUCCCAGCCCUAUGGAUGUGGGGUCCCCAUCAUCCCAGCUGCUCCCAAAUAAACUCCAGAAGAGGAAUCUGUGGGCCUGUGA